GUGUUUUUUUAAUACUAUGUGAGGCCUUGUCUUCCAUUGAAUAUUGGAAAGUUGGUAAUAAGCUUAGCUGGUCAGAAGUGAAAUGUGAGGUCCUUUGGCGAAAAAGUUUAAGGAGAAACUUCGGCUCUUUGGGUAAAGAGCAUGCGUUUACAGGGAUUAUUAUUAUUAUUUUUUUAAUUUUAAAGCAAGGAUAUAAAGCAGGGUCUUUGGUACUAUUUGGAGAAUUUAGACAGAAAAGAAGAAAGGAAAAGUAGUACCUGUUUACAUUUUCAUUUCCAUUUUUUCCCCUAAAGCUGUCCUGCGCAACAUGGUAGCCACUCACCGUAUUUGACUACUUAUAUUUAAAUUUAUGUAAAUUAAAAUGGAAUAAAAUUAAAUAUUCAGCCCUAGUCAUACUGGCCGUAUUUGAAGUGCUCACCGGCCACGGGUCUACUGGCUGCCUUGCCAAACGGAGCACCUGUGGAACACGCCAUCAACACAGAAAGUGCUAUUGGACAGUGCUGCUCAUAGCCUUAGAAUCCAAGAGAUUCCUGGACUCUUGGAGGCCCGUUGUAAAUCGUAGGGCCCCAGGAACCUAGGAGAGAAAGAGUUCUUACAGACAAACUUACAGAUGACCCUAAACAUGAAACAACAACAGUAACAAAGCUAGCUCAUCUACAAGGACCACUCUGAAGUCCUGUAAUCUGAAGAUGGAAGUCUCAUUUUACUGGCCCAGGCAACUAGUUCCUGGAAAGUUCGGUACAUGGAUGAUUUUUCUAGCUAGUUAGUGCUUGAUGUUAUUUACCAAGAUGUAUGAGACCUUGUUCCUUCGUGUGAGUAUUUUAACCUAGGCCAUUAUCUUUUUGCAAAAUGGGUAUAGUCAUCUUAGGGGAAUGUAGUGUGGGGCAAUGGAAUGUUUUUAUUACACCUCGAAAUCACAGUUGAAUGGUAUUUAUAGAGUUAUACUAAAAACUAUAUGAACUGGCUUUGGAAGUUUUUGUUUUUGUUUUUGUUGUUUUUUUGUUUGUUGUUGAGAUGGGGUCUCGCUUUGGCACCCAGGCUAGAAUGCAAAGUUGUGAUCAUGGUUCAUUUCAGUCUUGACCUCCUGGGCUCAGGCAGUCCUCCCACCUAAGCCUCCCAUGUAGCCGGGACCACAGGCAUGCGCCACCACACUGGCUAAUUUUUUUUUGGAUUUUUUUAUAGAGACAGGGUUUCAUCAUGUUGCCCAAGCUGGUCUUGAACUCCUGGGCUCAAGAUAUCCACCCACCUCAUCCUCCCAAAGUGCUAGGAUUACAGGGGUGAGCCACCGCGCCUAGCCUGGAAAUUCUGCAUAGGCUGAAAUUUAAGUCAUGUUACCCAUUGCUGUCUGUGAUGUAUCUGGACCUUCCAUUUGUUAGGCAGUAAUAUUUUUAGUGUAGGUGAGAAGUUCUGAUAUUCUAAUAUAAUCCCUAGAAAGUCUGUUUUCUAGAUUAUAGGAGUUGGCAAACCAUAGUUGGAGGGCCAAACCCAGCCUGUUUGUGUAAGUAAAGUUUUAUUGGAACACAGCCACUCCAUUUGUUUAUGAUUGUGUGUGGUUGCCUUAGCCCUACUAUUGCAGAGUUGCAGAAUUACAACAGACUGGCCUGCAAAACUGAAAAUAUUUACACUGUAGCCUUUGACAAAAAAAGCUUUGCCAGCCCCCAGUCCAGAUACUGGGUGAACGAUUGGAACGCCUUUCCAGUAAGGAAACAUCUGUGCAGGUCCAGGUUUGCCAGAGGAUUUUAGAGUAGAUGUGAGAUUUCCUUAUUCUUGGGCUAUAUAAUUUAGUAGACAAUAGAAAGGGUAAUUACACAUUAUACCUUUUUGGAUGUCAAAGACUUUUUUGGAUGUCAUUUCUCAGCGAUAACCUUACUUUCUACUUUCACUAAGGAAAUCUUGGAGUUUCACUCCAACAGGAGAUAAUUUUCACCGACUUCUCAUCUGCCAGGGUCUGUGCCCACUGCCUCCCACAGAUGAGCUGUUCGAACUGUUUGGCUGCUGUCUAAAGGCAAUGCUGAGCGCAUCCUGGGUCCUACCCUCCAGCCUUUUCCAGGCCAUCACUCCACCUCUCUCCCGCCUGUGUCACCUGAUUUGUCUUUCUGCUGGAUUGCUCCAUCAGGAUACACAUGUCCAUCCUCUGAAAAGAAACAGACACUCAGUGACCAUGUUCAUCUCACCAGCUGCCACCUUCCCCUGGCUCCUCUGUGUGUAAGCUCUCUUUCACAGGGCCAUUGGAGCUCGCUGUUUUCACCCUCAGCCAUUCUCUUUUGAACCCACUCUAGUUUUUGCCCCAGUCACUUGUUCCACAAAAGCUGCCUUGUCCAGGCCACUGUUGGUCCUCUGGUUGCUUAGACCAGUGGUCAGUUUUCAGUCUUCAUUAUGCUUGACAUGAUGACAGGGGUCUUCCCCCUGCUCCACCUGGCACAGUCUCUGCAUGAUAGCUGGGCCUUCUCUGUUGUCCUCCGCCCCCACCACUGCCUGUCCUCUGCAGGCCACUCCUCGUUCUUAUCUCCUGCACAUGGGAGAGCACAGAGUUCAGACCUGGGCCCUCUUCUCCCUCUGUACUUAUUCCUUGGGAGCUCGCAGCCAGUUUUAUGAAUUGAAAUACCACUGAUUUGCUUAUAACGUCCAAAUUCAUUCUUCCAGCCCUGCUCUCUCCCAUCCAAACUUCACACUUGUGUAUCAGCUGCCCAUCAGACACUUCUGUUUGGAUAUCUGCAAGACAUCUUAAACAUGACAUUGGCGAAAUGAGCUACUCUCCACCCACUUCAGGCUGCUACACCUUUUCUAGCCCAGGUGAUGGCAAGGCCAUGCUUUCAGUUCUUCAGGCUCCCAACGGUGGAACAUUGGAACCAUAUUCCCCACUCCCUCACCUCUCCGUCUCUCUCUCACUCUCUCACACAUACACACACCCAUACCCCCUUGCCACACACACAUCCCAAGUCUAGCUUGCUAGGAAAUUCUGUGGACUUUUCUCUUCAUAAAGCACCAGAAUCUGCCCCCUGCUCACUGCCUUCCUAGGAGCCACCAUCAGCUCUUUCCUGGAUUGCACCAACAGCCCUCAGUUUCCUCACCACCAUCCUUGCUUUACUAGAGUCUGUUGUCAACACAGUGAGCCUUUACAAAUAUAAGUUGGAUUAUGUCACUCUCCUGCUUAAAACUCACCCAAGGGUCCCAUUUCCCUUGGAGUCAAUGUCCAUACAGUGGCCUUGGGCAGCACACUCUGUCCCUCCCGUUACCUGCCCACCCACGCCUUCCCUCUGCUCCAGCUGUAUUAGUCUGUUUUCACGCUGCCAAUACAGACAUACCCACGACUGGACAAUUUACAAAAGAAAGAAGUUUAUUGGACUUUCGGUUCCACAUGGCUGGGGUUGCCUCACAAUCAUGGUGGAAGGUGAAAGGCACAUCUCACAUGGCAGCAGACAAGAGGAGAGUUUGUGCAGGGAAACUCCCCUCUUAAAAAUCAUCAGAUCUCGUGAGACUUAAUAUCACGAGAAUGGCAUGGGAAAGACCUGCCCCCAUGAUUCAAUUCCCUCUCACCAGGUCCCUCCCACAACACAUGGGAAUUCAAGAUGAGAUUUAGGUGGAGACACAGCCAAACCAUAUCACCAGCCAUACUGCCCACUGCCUUUUCUUAAACACACCAGGAACAUUUUUGCCUUGUUGCCCUGGCUCUUUCUUCUUCCUCUUCCCCUGUGUCUGUUCUCCUGACUCGCUCAUGUCUGUCAAGUCUGUGCUCAAAUGUCCAUUUUUUGUGUGAUCCACCCAGAUCACCUUGCUCUGUCUGCCUGCCUGCCUCCUGCCUACCCCCGGUUGCCUGGUCCCACUGAACACCACUCUACUUUUAUUUUCCCAUAGCCGCUUGGUAACCUCUAACAAACACUAUCCUUUCCUCCUGGUAAACUCUAAUCUUCCAGUGAUGGGGAUGUGUCUAUUUUGUUGAUUGCUAGAGUCCAAGUGUCUAGACCAGGGUCUAGCUACUAGUCCCCAGUACACAGUAGGAGCUCAGUACAUGUUUGCUGAAUGAGUGAAGGGGCCUGAUUCAGUCUAGUGCAGCCCUUCUUUGUAGCAGUGAAGGAAUAGCUCUCCUUUCUUCUUGAAGGGGGGUGAUGAGUUCCUUGGAGAUAAGAGGCAAGGCCGUUUAGCUUUAAUUUGUUUUUCUGUAGGUGGUGGGAGUGGGCUAUCUUUUCAAAGACACAUAUUCCAGAAUGGUCAGUACCAUGGUAUCUGCCGUCCUGGUCAUUGCCCGAGGAGCUUUUACAAUGACUAUGGAAUUAAGCGCCUGCAUCUGGGUGGCCUGCAGUUUGCCUUACUGAUAUGAUGGUAAGCUGGGGUCUCAGCAGAAGCUGCAGGGAUGAUACACAACUUUGUUGGCACUUUAGGUGAUGCACAUUUUGUCCUGACUGUCUUCCCUGGAGCUUUCUGUUCUAAGCAGAGCAGUUGAGUGUGUGGACAUUUGUUGUGUGCUGCUUUUGGCCGACAUCUCAGCUGGGACACAGCUGGGCCCUUGGGCCCAGAGGCAGCACAUUCACUGUACCCCUCAGAUUCUCAGCUGAAUAGCACCUGAAGUUCUUGUUAGCACUGAUUUUUUCCAUGUCAAGUUUGGCUAGUGACUGAGAUCCAUGAAGGCGAAGCCAUUUUAUCAUCCUUGGUGCACCAGGAUCCAGCUGGUCCCCACACUUAGCGGGGUUGCGUGAAUGUUCAUGGAGUCGUGAGUGAUACUGCCCCUAGCAAAGCCUCUCCAGACAUCAUAUGUUAGACAUCCCAGCAGCAUGUGAGCCUCUGCUAUUGUCUUACUGGACGAGCCCGUCGAGGAGACAGGGUGCACUCUUGCAGAGGAGCACACUGUUGUUUGCAUCAGCUUCGCUCUAUUAAACCUUCCCCUUGCUUAUCUCUGCUGGCCCAUCUAUGUUUUUUCACAUUAAUUUACUCUUCCGUUUGUCUUCAGUCCCCAUAACCUUUGAAUAAGCUGCUUACUGAUGAUCUUCCUUCCAUCAUAUUUAGGAUUUUGAAUAUCUACAUGUUUUUAAGCCAUAGAAAUGUAGAACUGGAGCUCAGUGGGCAAAGGCUUAAGUUCUGGAUCAGACUGAUGGGGCUCACAAACCAACGCUGCCAUAUGCCAAGUGUGUUCUCUUCCUUUUUGCACUUCAUUUUCCUCACCUUUAAACAGGUGAUAAUUGUGGACUCUGCUUCAUUUUCCGCCCUUAUAUGACCUUUUCAGUUUCAGUUCCCUUAGCUUCUAAAAGGCCAAGGUCAUGAAAUCUUUCUCUUUAUUUGAAGUUACAGUCCUCUUUAUGUUUUUGAUCAUUGAAUAUGUGACCUCCUGCUGCCUCCGUCUCUCCUCCCCACUCUGCAUCAGGGGAUAUUUCUCAAUAUUUGAUGUGAGGGUCCCUGAGGCCUUUGCUGACACUCCUCUCCACCUCUGGCCACUCUCUUUCUAUCACUCUCACCCACCCCUACUAGAAUAUGGGCUGCAACUAGGACAUGUAAGCUCUCAAGGGAAGGACGGAGUGUCCCUAUCACUGGAGCGUCAGCACCUAGAUCAGCCCCUCCUGUAACAAAGUGGGUGUUCAGUAAAUAGGUGAAUUAGACAGGGAUGGAUAAAUCAAUGAACAGAGUCCCUUCUUAGCUCCGUGAGAAGGCCACUUCCCAUUCCAGUCUGGCUCCUCAGUUUAGUGUAUGCCUUCUAUUGAACAGCUUGGCCCCCUGCCUGGAAAUUUGGGGGCUAGAUUUAAAAAGUGCCUGAGGGGAGAGGGAAGCGAUCCUGUGCUCUUCCUUGGGUUCCAGCAUUGCCUGGUUUCCCAGGACCCUCAGGCAGGGCUGCACUGAGGAGGGCUGGGCUGUGGACCCUGGGGAUCAAUAUCCCACCUUCACUGACCUCCAAAGGAGAGCAGCAAAACUAGGUGAAGAUUCAGGGAAUAGUUUCUUUGAGGGAAUGCUCACUGAGUUAAGUUGUGGACCUUGUAUUUUUCUCAAUAGCCUAGGGCUAAAGAAGCAGAUUGUCUUAGACCCAUAAAAGAUGAGGAAGCAGAUUGUUCUGGCAGAGUUCAGACUGGGGUUGGCAAUCCCGCUAUUUGUGCAAGCCAUGGGCUUGUGCCUCUCUGGGCAUCUGUUUGCAUGAAUUCAUGUCUUGUUCUUCUGACUGCAGAAGGAACAGGCAGGCCCCUGGAGAGAAAGAGAGAGAGGAACCUGGGUGGCGUUAGAGAAGAAGGUUUAGAAACCUGAGCUGAUAGAUCUGUUUUCAUGAAGGACUUCAUGUGACCUAUGGGCCUUCACAGGAUUUGUCAGGACUUGUGGGGAAAGUCCUGUACAGAACUGUGGAGGGGGCAUUCUCUGUACCUCUGCUUGGAAUCCAGCUGCCUUCUGGCAUCUUGGUGGAUCUUUGAGGAUAUCUUUGGGUCAGCACCAGCAUAUGGGGACUAAAGUAAUGGGGUAUGAGUAAAUGUUAAUCAAAUUGAAAUAGGGCUUCAUGACAAGCUGGCCAGGACAUCAGUCCCUGUUUCGGUCACCAUGCCUGACUUGUGUGACAAUCCUCCUUUAUCAUUCUGUCUGUGACUUGGAGCUCAGUUGACAAGUUCAGACUUGGUGCCAGUAGGAGGGUGGUUUUGGGCCCUGUACUGUUCAGAGUUAUGUGCGUGGGCUGUGGGAUCCAACAGACCCAGGCUUAAUUUCUGGCUUUGCUGUGUGGCCUUAGGGAAGUUUCUUACCUUCUAUAAGCUUUGGUUUUAUUUAUUUAUAUUUAUUUUAUAAAAUGGAAACAAUAAGCUCAUGGUGAGGAUUUAAGGAAAUCAAAGAGAUAAAGGGUUUUGUACAGUCUGAUAUUCGGUAGUUGUUACUGUUAGUGUUAUUAUACAUCAUGGUAUGCAAGUUGGAAUCCAGUUACUCCCAUAUAGAGUUAAUGGUUUUUAAUGUUUAUGCUUUUUAUAUAAGUUUGUUUAAAACUCACUUUCAGCCGCAAAAGUUUUGUAAGAGAGACUACUGUCAUUUCUUUUUUUUUUUUGGAGACAGAGUCUCACUCUGUCACCCAGGCUGGAGUGCAGUGGCACAAUCUCAGCUCACUGCAACCUUUGCCUCCCAGGUUCCAGUGAUUCUCGUGCCUCAGCCACCCAGAUAGCUAGGAUUACAGGUGUGUGCCACCACGCCUGGCUAAUUUUUGUAUUUUUAGUCGAGACAGGGUUUUGCCAUAUUGGCCAGGCUGGUCUCGAACUCCUGACCUCAAGUGAUCAGCCCACCUUGGCCUCCCAAAGUGCUGGGAUUACAGGCAUGAGCCACUGUACCCAGCCCCUAUUUCUCCAAAUGAAGAGACUGAGCCCCAAAAGGGUGAAGUCUGUUUCCUCAGCUUAUACAACUGGACCGAGGGAUGGAAGGCAAGCAUUUCGGGGGGACUGGCCCAGUGUACUUUAUUCAUGCUAGCAUCAAUGGUGAAUCCCAACACUUAAAAGCAUUUAUCACUUUGUUGAUCACAGACACACAGACACACCAAGUACCACAUAGGUGGUGUGUUUUUGAUCAGCUAGUCUCAGGGUCUCUCUGGGAAUUUAAUGGACUCAAACAGUUGCACAAGGUGCGACUGUAAGGUAACAGACGGCAUUUACAGAAAUCAGGCAGGAAAGACAAUCCCACCGCUUCAUAGACAUACUUCAUGUCAGCAUGGGGGCAGAGGUUCUACUGAGAGCUGACAUCUAUAGAACACUUCCCCUGCGCAUCCUCACUUAAUCCUCCCGGCAAGCCCACUGCUGUUUCCACGUUUUACAGAUGAGGAAAUGGCGCUCGGGGAGUUCAGUGACUUGCCCGAGCUGGAGCUGAGUGUAGUGACAGAGCCAGGCCUUGAACCCUGGCAGCCAGACUCCUCGCCCGUGCCGUCACCCUCUGUGCGGCCCUGGGGGGCGGUUGAUGAACACAGUUCAUCAAAAACGAACUGUGAUCCGACAGAUGAAAGCCGAGGUCUGUGAACAUGUGAAUGUUCUUUUGUGAACCGAAAUGUGCUUCAGUUGUUUUCUCUGUGUGUCAGGGAAGAGCGACCAUGAACUCCCAGCUCGUUGGGCAAAGGGCUGAUUUAUGAGGAUUUGCUCAACUCUAACCAGCUGGUUAACAACACGGAGCUUUUAACGUUUCCAGGGGAGGAAAUGAAUAAACAGGCAUUUGGGAUGAAGUCCACUGAGUCCGCGGGACUGGCUGAAAGGUGAAUUCAGUUGGAAGAAGUUUUGACAUACAAUGCAGACAUCUCUUGACCCAGUUUUGAAUCAGAGUUCUCAGUAAACAAAGUCAGGAAAUUAGAAUUUCUGGGUCAAUUCCACAUUUCAUAAGCAACGUCAAAAGAAAUAUUUAUUUUGUGGGAAGGUUACCUGGUUUAGGUGGAAUAAGUCAGACGGAAAAGCAAAAUUAGUUACCCAGAUGAUGGGUGUUCUUUAUUGAUUUUAAAUUCAGUAAAAUUGCCAUCAGAAAUUCUCAAUUAUAACAUUUAUGUUUUAUCUAGUAUUUUAACUAUAAAUGGCUUGUACAUAUUUGAGAGUCUUUUAUCCUAUGGAAUACUUGAAACCAUGCUGCAUUUAAUUUAAUUUUUUUUAGAAAAUCAAAUAUCACCAGCUAUCUGCUUUCCAUUUGCCUUUUGGCCUUUUGGAAAAAUACAAAAUUAGGAUAUUUUGGUAGAAUUAACAUAGCAGGCCAAAAUUUCUGUAAUCCUUUAGUGAUUUCUCAGAAAUAAAAGCCAUGUGGCAGUGGUCAAGCUUGUGCCCAGCAUAAAAUGACUAAAAGUGUAAACUGGUAAGGGGCUGAUAUAGACCAGCUCUGCUUCUGUUCUUGAGUUCUCUUAGCGUGUACUUUGCUUCCUCAUCUCCCCUGGGUAACUCCCCUGUUGCAGGGAACAUGGACCCUUCCUGAGAGCCAGUGGCUGUGCUAGAGUUGAUCAUGUUCCCAAAGAGUUCUCUGAGCUUCCUUCUGCUUUGGGGGAAUGAGAGGUUCUGAAAGUCUUUUGUGCUCGUGAAAGGAGCCUGGUUUAGAAGGCUCUCAUCAGACUCUGGCAGGAUCAUUCAGGUUACACAUAAAAAAAGGGAAAGAGGACAGGAAAAUACAGGAAAAAAAUGACUGGAGAAUAUUAUAAUAUUUAUUUGCUUCUAAAUCAGAAUAAAUGGGCAGCUUUCCACAAAAGCCAAAAUAGACAGUACCCUCGUUACCUGGAUCUGUGCAGGACAUUCAUCCAUUCAUGCUGCUAGUUUUAUUGCAAAGACUGAACAAGUCAUAUUAAUGCAAUUUUAAAAAAAUAGGGCCAGACUGGGCUUUAGAAAUAAGUAACUUAAAGUUGCUUGGGACAUGAGGGGACAUGAAGAGAGAGAAAAGAUUUCUGUCUCUGUGUUAGGCAUUUCAACUGAUUCUUUUAGAAUAUUUUUUGCCCGCCGUGUCUGUCAACGAUGGCUUGGCUAAUGCAGCCUAGUGCUCGUGGAGGUUGCAUCUCUCCAAGUCAGCCAGGCAUCAAGUAUUUCACCAGCACUUAUGGUACAUCUACCUGUGGGAGAAUGCAACAUAAAAAUAUACCCGUCGUUGUGACAAUUUGACUUGCAGGGAAGAGUAAGGUCUACAGUGUGCUCAGUGGGCUACCCUGCAGAGGGCAGGCACUACCGGGUAAGGGCACUGGACUUCUUGUUCACUUGUCCGUGGUCCUUUCUCUCUCCUUCUGACUGCUGCUUCCCAGGGAUGGGGUUUGGGCUACUUCAUCCCAAGUCUGUUUUCAUAAUUGUAAAAUGUGGAAUAAUCUUCAUAAUUUGCAAGGUUGCUGUGAGAGUGAUAUUAGGUAGAAGGUGAAUGGCUCUUUGAGAGUCAUAAAUGGCUUGUGCUUUGUUAAAUAGAAGGUGAUAAUAGCCAAGUAAUGAAAUGUGUUAACUUUACUCACGGAAAACUCUCAGCUCCACUGCUGAAAACUCAUCCCCUUCUCCCAGGCAACCAUUUGGAGGCCCAGGCCAGAGGCUGGACCAGGAGGAUUGGAUGCAUCCGCGCUGUCCAUCCCUGCUGCUGCACAAACGACUCAGCCACAGAUCCUCUUGGAUGGGCUACCUUGAAAGGGGGAAGCUCCAAAGAAUGCGUACAAACCCAUACAUUUACCUAGAGGAUGAAAGUCCUGGACAGACUUAUCACAGAGAGAGAAGAAACGCAAUCACUAUGCAGCCACAGAAUGUCCAGGGGCUCAGCAAAGUCAGUGAGGAACCUUCAACAUCGAGUGACGAGAGGGCCUCAUUGAUCAAGAAAGAGAUCCAUGGGUCCCUGCCACACGUGGCGGAGCCCUCUGUGCCGUACCGCGGGACGGUGUUUGCCAUGGACCCCAGGAAUGGUUACAUGGAGCCCCACUACCACCCUCCUCAUCUUUUCCCUGCCUUCCAUCCUCCUGUACCAAUUGAUGCCAGACAUCAUGAGGGCCGUUACCAUUACGAUCCAUCUCCGAUUCCUCCAUUGCAUAUGACUUCCGCCUUAUCUAGUAGCCCUACGUAUCCGGACCUGCCCUUCAUUAGGAUCUCCCCACACCGGAACCCCACUGCUGCUUCCGAGUCUCCCUUCAGCCCUCCACAUCCCUACAUUAAUCCCUACAUGGACUAUAUCCGCUCCUUGCACAGCAGCCCAUCGCUCUCCAUGAUCUCAGCAACCCGUGGGCUGAGCCCUACAGAUGCGCCCCAUGCAGGAGUCAGCCCAGCAGAAUACUAUCAUCAGAUGGCCCUGCUAACUGGCCAGCGCAGCCCCUAUGCAGACAUUAUUCCCUCAGCUGCCACCGCCGGCACGGGGGCCAUCCACAUGGAAUAUCUUCAUGCUAUGGAUAGCACCAGAUUCUCCAGCCCCAGGCUGUCAGCCAGGCCGAGCCGAAAACGUACACUGUCCAUAUCACCACUCUCCGAUCAUAGCUUUGACCUUCAGACCAUGAUAAGGACGUCUCCCAACUCCUUGGUCACGAUUCUCAAUAAUUCCCGUAGCAGCUCUUCAGCAAGUGGCUCCUAUGGUCACUUAUCUGCAAGUGCAAUCAGCCCUGCCUUGAGCUUCACCUACUCUUCCGCGCCCGUCUCUCUCCACAUGCAUCAGCAGAUCCUAAGCCGACAACAGAGCUUAGGUUCAGCCUUUGGACACAGCCCUCCACUCAUCCACCCUGCCCCAACUUUUCCAACACAGAGGCCUAUUCCAGGGAUCCCUACGGUUCUGAACCCCGUCCAGGUCAGCUCCGGCCCUUCUGAGUCCUCACAGAACAAGCCCACGAGUGAGUCUGCAGUGAGCAGCACUGGUGACCCGAUGCACAACAAGAGGUCCAAGAUCAAACCCGAUGAAGACCUCCCCAGCCCAGGGGCUCGGGGGCAGCAGGAACAGCCCGAAGGAACAACCCUUGUCAAGGAGGAAGGGGACAAAGAUGAAAGCAAACAGGAGCCUGAAGUCAUCUAUGAGACAAACUGCCACUGGGAAGGCUGCGCGAGGGAGUUCGACACCCAAGAGCAGCUUGUGCACCAUAUAAAUAACGACCAUAUUCAUGGAGAGAAGAAGGAGUUCGUGUGCAGGUGGCUGGACUGCUCAAGAGAGCAGAAACCCUUCAAAGCCCAGUAUAUGUUGGUAGUGCAUAUGAGAAGACACACGGGCGAGAAGCCUCACAAAUGCACUUUUGAAGGUUGCACAAAGGCCUACUCGAGACUAGAAAACUUGAAAACACACUUGAGAUCUCACACUGGAGAGAAACCAUACGUCUGUGAGCACGAAGGUUGCAACAAGGCUUUCUCAAAUGCCUCUGAUCGCGCCAAACACCAAAACAGAACGCAUUCCAAUGAGAAACCAUAUGUGUGCAAAAUCCCAGGCUGCACUAAGCGUUACACAGACCCAAGCUCCCUCCGGAAACAUGUGAAGACAGUGCAUGGCCCAGAGGCUCAUGUCACCAAGAAGCAGCGAGGGGACAUCCAUCCUCGGCCGCCACCCCCGAGAGAUUCCGGCAGCCAUUCACAGUCCAGGUCGCCUGGCCGACCGACUCAGGGAGCCCUUGGUGAGCAGCAGGACCUCAGCAACACUACCUCAAAGCGGGAAGAAUGCCUCCAGGUGAAAACCGUCAAGGCAGAGAAGCCAAUGACAUCUCAGCCAAGCCCUGGUGGUCAGUCUUCAUGCAGCAGCCAACAGUCCCCCAUCAGCAACUAUUCCAACAGUGGGCUCGAGCUUCCUCUGACCGAUGGAGGUAGUAUAGGAGACCUCAGUGCCAUCGAUGAAACCCCAAUCAUGGACUCAACCAUUUCCACUGCAACCACAGCCCUUGCUUUGCAAGCCAGGAGAAACCCGGCAGGGACCAAAUGGAUGGAGCACGUAAAACUAGAAAGGCUAAAACAAGUGAAUGGAAUGUUUCCGCGACUGAACCCCAUUCUACCCCCUAAAGCCCCUGCGGUCUCUCCUCUCAUAGGAAAUGGCACACAGUCCAACAACACCUGCAGCUUGGGUGGGCCCAUGACGCUUCUCCCGGGCAGAAGCGACCUCUCUGGGGUGGACGUCACUAUGCUGAACAUGCUCAACAGAAGGGACAGCAGCGCCAGCACCAUCAGCUCGGCCUACCUGAGCAGCCGCCGCUCCUCAGGGAUCUCGCCCUGCUUCUCCAGCCGCCGCUCCAGCGAGGCGUCACAGGCCGAGGGCCGGCCGCAGAACGUGAGCGUGGCCGACUCCUACGACCCCAUCUCCACCGACGCCUCGCGCCGCUCCAGCGAAGCCAGCCAGAGCGACGGCCUGCCCAGCCUGCUCAGCCUCACGCCCGCCCAGCAGUACCGCCUCAAGGCCAAGUACGCGGCUGCCACAGGAGGGCCGCCGCCGACGCCCCUGCCCAACAUGGAGAGGAUGAGCCUGAAGACGCGCCUGGCGCUGCUCGGGGAUGCCCUCGAGCCUGGCGUGGCCCUGCCUCCAGUUCAUGCCCCGAGGAGGUGCAGCGACGGGGGAGCCCACGGCUACGGGCGGCGCCACCUGCAGCCGCACGAUGCGCCGGGCCACGGCGUGAGGAGGGCCAGCGACCCGGUGCGGACAGGCUCCGAGGGCCUGGCCCUGCCUCGUGUGCCGCGCUUCAGCAGCCUCAGCAGCUGCAACCCCCCGGCGAUGGCCACGUCCGCGGAGAAGCGCAGUCUCGUGCUUCAGAAUUACACGCGGCCCGAGGGCGGCCAGUCCCGAAACUUCCACUCGUCCCCCUGUCCUCCCAGCAUCACCGAGAACGUCACCCUGGAGUCCCUGACCAUGGACGCUGAUGCCAACCUGAACGAUGAGGAUUUCCUGCCGGACGACGUGGUGCAGUAUUUAAAUUCCCAGAACCAAGCAGGGUACGAGCAGCACUUCCCCAGCGCCCUCCCGGACGACAGCAAAGUGCCCCACGGGCCCGGUGACUUUGACGCGCCCGGGCUGCCAGACAGCCACGCUGGCCAGCAGUUCCAUGCCCUCGAGCAGCCCUGCCCCGAGGGCAGCAAAACCGACCUGCCCAUUCAGUGGAACGAAGUCAGCUCCGGAAGCGCCGACCUGUCCUCCUCCAAGCUCAAGUGUGGGCCGCGGCCCGCUGUGCCGCAGACUCGCGCCUUUGGGUUCUGCAACGGCAUGGUCGUCCACCCGCAGAACCCCUUGAGGAGCGGGCCUGCUGGGGGCUAUCAGACCCUCGGGGAGAACAGCAACCCCUACGGUGGCCCAGAGCACUUGAUGCUCCACAACAGCCCCGGAAGUGGCACCAGUGGAAACGCCUUCCAUGAACAGCCCUGUAAGGCCCCGCAGUAUGGGAACUGUCUCAACAGGCAGCCAGUGGCCCCUGGUGCACUCGACGGUGCCUGUGGUGCCGGGAUUCAAGCCUCAAAGCUGAAGAGCACCCCCAUGCAAGGGAGCGGGGGCCAGCUGAAUUUCGGCCUGCCGGUAGCGCCAAAUGAGUCAGCUGGCAGCAUGGUGAAUGGCAUGCAGAACCAGGACCCAGUGGGACAGGGGUACCUGGCUCACCAGCUCCUCGGCGACAGCAUGCAGCACCCGGGGGCAGGCCGCCCCGGUCAGCAGAUGCUUGGGCAGAUUAGUGCUACCUCACACAUCAACAUCUACCAAGGGCCAGAGAGCUGCCUGCCAGGGGCUCACGGCAUGGGCAGCCAGCCGUCAAGCUUGGCAGUUGUCAGGGGCUACCAGCCAUGUGCCAGCUUUGGGGGCAGCAGGCGCCAGGCUAUGCCGAGGGACAGCCUUGCUCUGCAGUCAGGACAGCUCAGUGACACAAGUCAGACCUGCAGGGUGAAUGGUAUCAAGAUGGAGAUGAAAGGGCAGCCCCAUCCGCUGUGCUCUAAUCUGCAGAAUUACUCUGGUCAGUUCUAUGACCAAACCGUGGGCUUCAGUCAGCAAGACACGAAAGCUGGUUCAUUCUCUAUUUCAGACGCCAGCUGCCUGCUACAGGGGACCAGCGCCAAAAACUCUGAGUUACUUUCCCCAGGUGCUAAUCAGGUGACAAGCACAGUGGACAGCCUCGACAGCCAUGACCUGGAAGGGGUACAGAUUGACUUCGAUGCCAUCAUAGACGAUGGGGACCACUCCAGCCUGAUGUCGGGGGCCCUGAGCCCAAGUAUCAUUCAGAACCUUUCCCAUAGCUCCUCCCGCCUCACCACGCCUCGGGCGUCCCUCCCAUUCCCAGCGCUGUCCAUGAGCACCACCAACAUGGCUAUCGGGGACAUGAGUUCUUUGCUGACCUCCCUAGCGGAAGAAAGCAAAUUCCUUGCAGUUAUGCAAUAGGCUUUAGGAAAAAAAGACUGCAACCAACGGAAAUCAAUAGGAGUUGAAGAGAUUAAACUGACUUUGUUUUGGCUGUUUUUUUAGUUCUGUAUGUAUUUUAGCAAUCUCAUCUCACCUAACUGAGAUGUGUUUCAAUUAUAUUCCUUUUAUGGAAAAGGACUCUGAAAAACCCUAAAGUAUUCUAGGGAGAAACUGUCUUCCAUUUCAGUUUUGAAUCAGUAUUGUUACACUCAAACCACCCUCUUUUUAAAAAAAAAAAAAAAAACUGUAAGCCCCGCCCCCUUUUUAGUAAACCGAUGUAAAUUUGUGAUGUGCAUAUUCUUCUUUCUUUUAGAAGAGCAGUCAAAUUAAAGGAUUUGACAUGUUUUGCUGUUGCUCAAAGGAAAUAGGAGUUGGUGUGCUUGUGACCAAGGGGUUACACUUCCAGCUUUUAAAAUUCUCCUUUACAUGUGCUCAGUGUUUUGUUUUGUGUUUUGGUUUCUGUUUUUUAUUUUAAUUCCCACAUUGGGCACAAGAAUCAGAAUAUGGAUAGCUAGUUUAAGAAACUUUUGUGGGUGCACUGUAGCAUAGAUGACAGAAUAUUGAUGUUCCCCCCAUCUCCAAUUCAGUUCAGGGCAUUCCACAGUUAAACAGAAAUGGGAACGUGGGGCUCUUAUAAAUGAAAUGGGCGCUCACAGUUUUGGUUUUCAGCUCUUCAUGUCUGUAAGUGUGCUUUGGGGGAGGCUAUGUCUGUAUGGUCGAUUCUCAGUUAUCACAUUUGCCUCUCCUCCCACUACCUUCAUGAACAUUCAGUGCUGUUUCGCACUGCAGUUAGAGAGAAGGGACGGACAGUUGGUGACACUCAGCCACAUUGCUACUUUUAUCUGUUCUGGUAAGAAGUUAGAUAGAUGGUAGAUUGAAGCAAUUGGGUAGAAUUAGUUGGGGGAAUAUUUAUGAGUUGCUGUGUUUGUUGAUUAGUUCCAUCUCUUUCCCAUUUUAACUGAGAAUUGAUUAUAUAUAGCUCUAAGUAUAUAGGUAUUUAAACAACCCCACAAGCGGCUGUAUCAGUAACAUUUAUUAAUUCCACUAUAGUGAGGGAGGAUUUCCAUUCUAAAUACCUUAUUUUGAGGGAUUUAUAAAACUUAGUUGUAAAAGAGAAAGCCCACAUAGUGGGAAUAAAUUGCUUCAGCCAUUUUUAGUAUUUGAGAGCACUAGGGAAGAUGUUUAGUAGCUGUGUGGAUGCCUUUUUUCACACCCUGUCUAUUGAAUGCUGCAUCCAUUCACGAAGUUAAAUGUUACAUGCAGUUAGUCCUUAAUGUGGACUGGAUCUGUACUUUUGUUUUGGAUUAAAACAUUUAAAGAUUUUUGAAGUGCAGCUACUCCCCACGUGCAUUUGAUACACAUAAAAGUCAUACUGUGUGUGCACAAAGAGUACAUGGAUUUUCCAGCAUAUUGCUUUAAAAAAUUAUAUAAACUGUUAAAAUAUUAACACCUCAGGCUACCUGCUGUAUUCUGUCCCAUUGACCCCUGGAAUUGGAUUUACUGCAAGUGAUUGAUAAUUCAAUUAUGUGGCUUUUCCCCUUUAAUCUUGCCAUUUAAAUUACAGUAGAAAGACAAAAUCAAGUAAAAUAAAGUGUUAGAUAAUAGAAAGAGUGUUAAGACCAGCCCACUUUUCUCAUGUUUAUGUUCUUUCAUUUGGACCAAGAAUCUCCGCAUGGAGGUUGAUUUGCCACUGGGGACUUUGGCUAAGACUAUUAGGUUUGCUUUCAACUAGAUGUUCCUGAGACAAGCAGAGGGACACUGCAAUUCCCCUUCCAUGCCUGCUGUUCUCCCCCAUGUAAGUCUUCUUUGAAAUUAACGGAUGUGUCUCCUUUGGAACAGCCCCAUAACAAAAGAGAACUACUGAUCUGAGCAUAGGAAAGUAGAGGCUCUACCACUUUUCAGUUGAAAAAGCAAGACUUUCUCUGUGUUUCUGAAACAAGGCAUAAUGUUGUCACAGAAUCAGAGAUCCAGUCUCACUUUUCCACAAAUCUCCAAAUCUCCAGUCUUAUCUUGUGUGCUCUAAUGGUUUGGUUCAAUCCCUUUCCAACUCUUGUUUUCAAAGCAUGGGGCCUGAGUGUUCUCCACUCCUCCUAAGAAAGGAGCUUGGGUGGAAGGGACCAUGCUGACCUCCUCCAUCAGAGGGCUCUUCCAGUAGUAUUCUCGGAUGCAACCUCCAUUUCUCAGUUACCAUUAUUUCCUGUAUCAGCUUUGUCCUUCCUGGAGGGAUGCACAGUGAUCCGGCCCACCACUGUUGUUGUCUUGUGCUUCUGCUCUUUCCUAUGGUUUCAGGUUAUUUUCUGGGUUUCCCCUAUUCUUCUUUUAUUUCUUUUUUUUUUUAUAUUUGCUUUCCUUUCUACUGCUUUUAGAUUUGCAGGAGAUGCAAGUUUCAGCUCAAUGUUUGGCUUCUCUCAAUAUGGAAAUUUCAGAAGGACAGAGGAGAGGAGGGAGGAAGAAGAAAGUAUACUCCUCCAGAAUUUCAGUGAUCUGUUGUGGCAGUCCAGUGGAAGGAAGGUCUUUUGAGGUCACUUAGAAGCAUCUUUUUGGGACAUCCUUUUGGGAUCUCUGUAGGCUAGGCAUCUCAUAUCUUGAGACUCACCCCCAGCCUCCAAGCCUCUCUCCAUUUCUCUAACCUAUGCAUUUUAGAGCGAGAGGACCGCCUCACUAGUGUCACCAUCCUGCCUUUUCUAAAACAUGCAGGCUCACACAUUCUACUCCUGCUUAAUGUCUGUGUUAAACGUUUUCUAACCAUUUUUGUUUUAUUUUUCUGAAAAAGUUAACCCCUCCCAACUCCUCACACAUUGGCUCUUCCUCUUGAGCCACAAAGUUUUGAUUCUUGCGAUGUAUGUGCCUUAUUUUAUGUUAAUCUUGUCAAUGAGAGGGACCAGUUGGUGUUGCCCAAUCAGCACUCCAAGGCUGUGUGUGCACCAGCCAGAGAGCGCACGGUGGUAGCAGAGUCGAGGCUGUCUUGUAUCCUGGUUUCAUGUGUUGUUUUGAACUGAUAGGAGGAUGUUCUCUUCUGACAAGUUACCCUUGUGUAUCCUGCAGACAUGUAAAAUAAAAUACAAGUUCAUUUUUUUCACCUUUUUUAGAUUUUUUUAAAAAAUAAAAUGUGUAAUCCUUUUUUUAAAAGAAACACAUGUAAAUACAUUUAAGUAUUGUAGGCAUAGCGUUCAGAUGUGACUGGCCCAGGCGUUCCUCGGACAAGCCUGCAUUCCCCGUGAUCACGCCCACCUCAAGCCCAGGGGCUGCAGCCCAGCCACAGAUGAACUCUACCUUUGCUUUCAGAACCACUUAGUCCUUUUGUAACAAAGAAAAAAAAAUGUUUCUUACAAUGUCAAUAAAAAAUUCUUUGUAUGGAAA